UUCAAGGUUGUUUUGGCUAUUUGGAGCACCUUGCAAUUCCACAAGAAUUUGGGGAUUGGCUUUUUCAUUUCUUUUAACAACAACAAAAAAAAAGCUUUUGGAAUUUUGGAUCUGUGUGGGGGAUUGUGUUGGAUCUGUAAGCUGAUAUUUCAUCCAAGCAAUAUUAAUUUUCUAAUCCAUGAACAGAGGAUGUCUUUUCAUUUGCUUAUGUCUGAUUUUUCUUAGCAGUGUUUUAUAUUUUCUAGUUUACAGUCCUUUCACCUCCCUGGUAAAGUUUCUUCCUAGAUAUGUUAUUCUUUUUGAUGCUGUUGUAAGUGGAAUUUUUUGUUUGUUUGUUUCUGGAUUGUCCAUUGUGGUGUAUGGAAACAUAACUGAUUGUGUGUUGAUCUUGUAUUGUGCAACUUUGCUGAAUUUCUGUAUUAGCUGUAGUAACCUUCGUUUAUAAUCUCUGGGAUUUUCUAUAUAUAGGACUAUGUCAUCUGUGGUUAGUGAUAGUCUAACAUCUUCCUUUCCAAUUUGGAUGCCUUUUUCUUCUCCUUAACUGAUUGCCCUGCAUAGGAUUUCCAGUGCAGUGUUGAAUGGCAGUGGUGAAGGGGCAUCCUUGUUCUGCUCCUGAUCUCGGGGAAAGCUUCCAGUCUUUUCUAUUGAGCAAGUUCCUUGAUACUCCUUGUGUUCCCAGUGGUUUUAUCAUGUGGAUUUUGUCAAUGCCUUUUCUGUAUCAGUUAAGAUGAUCACGUGGUUUCUCUCCUUCAGUCUAUCUGUCAGUGUGGUGUUUUACACUGGUUGGUCUCAUGUUGAACCGGCCCUGAGCGUGUAUUCCGGUUGUCACAGCAGCAUCUGUGUGCUUUUGAAAAACAGAGGAACCUCCCUGUGGGCUUUCAUAUGAUCCAUGAAACCCACGUGAGCAAUCUCAUGCCUGCAGUUAAACACACACCAGAGCAGGCCAGGAGUCCUUGGCCCUCCAGCGGCAUUUCCCAAAGGAGAUGAUACUGAAAGGUACAGAAUUUAGACUGUUGUAGAGGUUAAGGAAUAAAAGACAUUCGUGGCGUGUACAGGUGGAGCUCCGUGGAAAGGUGACUGCAGCAUCUGGUUUAUGGUUUAAAUGGCAUAAGUGAAAAACAAACCUGUUGGUUUGCUGUAAAUACUGACUGCAGUUAAAUCCUAUGGUCCCUCUGGAGAACAACUUCUCCCAGCCAGAGACGGGCAGGAGCUCAUCUUGCACAAGUCGAAGCCAGAUUUUGAGAAUCGUGAAUCAUUUUAAGAAACAAGCGGACGAGCGGACUUGGCGUUAACAUUUUAAAAAUAACUCUCCCUCAAGAGCCUGUGCUGUGCUGCUGCGCUGGAACCUCCGGCUUCCUCUCACUGAACAGAAUGGACGGCUUCGGGCCUGCGCAGAACUUCUCAGAGAAUUGCUCUUCACCACCAGGAGUGUUCCUUGAGAAGGACUAUGAGAUUUACCGGGAUUACAGUGCGGACGGCCAGCUUCUUCACUACAGGACCUCCUCGCUGCGGUGGAACUCGGGCGCCAAAGAGCGCAUGCUCAUCAAGGUCGCUGAUCGGGAGCCCAGCUUCCUCGCCGCCCAGGGCAAUGGCUACGCCCCAGACGGCCCACCUGGGGUCCGCUCCCGCAGACCCUCCGGCAGCCAGCACUCACCCAGCCUGCAGACCUUCGCCCCGGAGGCUGACGGCACCAUCUUCUUCCCAGAGAGGAGGCCGUCACCCUUCCUGAAGAGGGCCGAGCUCCCAGGGAGCAGCUCCCCGCUGCUGGCCCAGCCCCGAAAGCCCUCCGGGGACUCGCAGCCCUCCUCCCCGCGCUAUGGCUAUGAACCCCCGCUCUACGAGGAGCCCCCAGUGGAGUACCAGGCCCCCAUCUACGAUGAGCCCCCCAUGGACGUGCAAUUCGAGGCUGGCGGGGGCUACCAGGCCGGCUCUCCCCAGCGGUCGCCGGGCCGUAAGCCCCGGCCGUUCCUCCAGCCCAACAAGCAGGGCCCCCCCUCGCCCUGCCAGCAGCUGGUGCUCACCAAGCAGAAGUGUCCCGAGCGCUUCCUGAGCCUGGAGUACAGUCCCGCCGGCAAGGAGUACGUGCGGCAGCUGGUCUACGUGGAGCAGGCGGGCUCCAGCCCCAAGCUGCGCGCCGGCCCGCGGCACAAGUACGCGCCCAACCCCGGCGGUGGUUCGUACUCCUUGCAGCCCAGCCCCUGCCUGCUGAGGGACCAGCGCCUGGGCGUCAAGUCCGGAGACUACAGCACCAUGGAGGGACCUGAGCUGCGGCACAGCCAGCCGCCCACGCCGCUGCCACAGGCCCAGGAGGAUGCCAUGUCCUGGUCCAGCCAGCAGGACACCCUGUCCUCCACAGGCUACUCCCCGGGCACGCGCAAGCGGAAGAGCAGAAAGCCCUCUUUGUGCCAAGCCACCAGCGCCACCCCCACUGAGGGCCCCGGGGACCUGCUUGUGGAGCAGCCCCUGGCCGAGGAACAGCCCCCGUGCGGGACCAGCCUCGCCCCCGUGAAGCGAGCGGAAGGUGAGGCCGAAGGGGCGCGGGGCGCGGCCGAGCCCUUCCUGGCGCAGGCUCGGCUGGCCUGGGAGGCGCAGCAGGCCCACUUCCACAUGAAGCAGAGGAGCAGCUGGGACUCCCAGCAGGACGGCUCUGGCUACGAGAGCGACGGCGCCCUGCCACUGCCCAUGCCCGGGCCGGUGGUGCGGGCCUUCAGCGAGGACGAGGCGCUGGCCCAGCAGGAGAACAGGCACUGGAGGAGGGGCACCUUCGAGAAGCUAGGCUUCCCCCAGAUCCUGCUGGAGAAGAGCGUCUCCGUGCAGACCAACCUGGCCUCACCAGAGCCCUACCUCCACCCCUCACAGUCUGAGGACCUCGCUGCCUGUGCCCAGUUCGAGAGCAGCCGGCAGAGCCGCAGCGGCGUUCCCAGCUCCAGCUGCGUCUUCCCCACUUUCACGCUGCGCAAGCCCUCCUCGGAGACGGACAUCGAGAACUGGGCCUCCAAGCACUUCAACAAGCACACGCAGGGCCUCUUCCGGCGGAAGGUGUCCAUCGCCAACAUGCUGGCCUGGAGCAGCGAGUCCAUCAAGAAGCCCAUGAUCGUGACAAGCGACCGGCACGUGAAGAAGGAGGCCUGCGAGCUCUUCAAGCUGAUCCAGAUGUACAUGGGUGACCGGCGGGCCAAGGCCGACCCACUGCACGUGGCCCUGGAGGUGGCCACCAAGGGCUGGAGCGUGCAGGGCCUGCGGGACGAGCUCUACAUCCAGCUGUGCCGGCAGACCACCGAGAACUUCCGCCUGGAGAGCCUGGCCCGCGGCUGGGAGCUCAUGGCCAUCUGCCUGGCCUUUUUCCCGCCCACCCCCAAGUUCCACUCCUACCUGGAAGGCUACAUCUACCGGCACAUGGACCCCGUCAAUGACACUAAAGUGACACAGCACAUAAAAGAGCUCCUGGAAAGAAACACUAAGAAGAAGUCCAAAUUGAGAAAGAAACCCAAGCCUUAUGUUGAAGAGCCGGAUGGGGUGGCGAUAAGCACGUAUGCCAAGUACUGUUACCACAAGCUACAGAAGGCAGCCCUGACCGGGGCCAAGAAGGGGCUGAAGAAGCCCAACGUGGAGGAGAUCCGGCAUGCCAAGAACGCCGUGUUCAGCCCGUCCAUGUUCGGCAGCGCACUGCAGGAGGUCAUGGGCAUGCAGAGAGAGCGCUACCCCGAGCGCCAGCUGCCCUGGGUGCAGACACGGCUCUCUGAGGAGGUGCUGGCGCUCAACGGUGACCAGACAGAGGGCAUCUUCAGGGUCCCUGGGGACAUUGACGAGGUGAAUGCCCUGAAGCUGCAGGUGGACCAGUGGAAGGUGCCCACAGGCCUGGAAGACCCCCACGUCCCUGCGUCCCUGCUGAAGCUGUGGUACCGGGAGCUGGAGGAGCCCCUGAUCCCGCACGAGUUCUACGAGCAGUGCAUCGCGCACUACGACAGCCCCGAGGCGGCGGUGGCCGUGGUGCACGCGCUGCCCCGCAUCAACCGCAUGGUGCUGUGCUACCUCAUCCGCUUCCUGCAGGUCUUCGUGCAGCCGGCCAACGUCGCGGUCACCAAGAUGGAUGUCAGCAACCUGGCCAUGGUGAUGGCGCCCAACUGCUUGCGCUGCCAGUCCGACGACCCGCGCGUCAUCUUCGAGAACACCCGCAAGGAGAUGUCCUUCCUGCGGGUGCUCAUCCAGCACCUGGACACCAGCUUCAUGGAGGGUGUGCUGUAGCGGGGGCGCCCGGGGACAGGAGGGAUGUCCUGCCGCCCCCAGCCAGGCCGAACUCCGCACUCGCUCUCCCGGCAGAGGGGCCAGAAUCGCCCGGCCCAGCCCUGGAGCCCCCUCCACUCCCCCAGGCCCCUGGCCCCGGCGCUCCCCACGUCUUCUGCCUGGUCUGAGGGUGCAGCCAGGGCACAGCAGCGGCGGGGAGGGCGCCUCUGGCCCCCCACCUCACGGCCAGUUCCCGCGGGCACCGCCUCGCCCUCCGCUGGCCGCGGGUCAGCUCCGAGAAAGUGCCUUCUGUGUCCUGGAGCCGAGCGACGCUGCCUCCUUGGGGCCGGGCUGCCUCCCUGUGGCUCCUGCGCGCCCUGGCCUGGGCCUUGCCCAGCCGCCCCGGUCUCUCCUUCCCUUUCUCCUGUCCUCGUCCUGGCCUGCAGCUCUUCCCAGCCCCGAGAGAGCUUCCCGACCUGUCCCCGCCUCCUCUCCCUCCCUCGGCCCGUGGUCCCCAGCUGGUGACUGCUCAGGAGUUUGGGGGCUCCAGGACAGUGGGCCCGGGGCCUGGCAGGCUCUCGGUGGGUGGGGUGGGGGCCCCCAAACCAAAGUCCUCUGGGGUAGGGAGCAGGGCUGGGCAGGCAUUCUGGGGGCAGGGUGGGGGAGGGGCGAGAGUAUUUUUUUCUUCGUGUAACUGUAAAUCCAGAAUCUAUCCUGCAUCGCAGCCCACCGUGUAUAGAGAUAUAAAUAGAGGGAAAGAUAUAAGAACUAAAUUUGCUAAUGACAUAGUUUUAACCUAAAUGCUAUUUAUCUCUGAGCCGUCCCCGUCCUCCGUGCAGAGCAAGUUGAGGUCAUUCCUUCUUUUCUUCUCCGAUCUUUUUUCUUGGCUUCUGACCAAAAACCAAGCUCUACCCCAUCCCCAUCCCAGACCUGCAGGAGACGAGCGAGCGGGAAGGCGCCGGGCCCGGGACUGUCCGUUCUCGGGGCCAGAGCUGCUGGGGGACCGAGUUUGUACAUUUUCCAUUUUGGAAUUUUGAGUUCCAAUUGUUGUAAAACUUAAUUUCUCCCCAGUUUUUAUAUAUAUAUUUUUUAGAGUUCCGUUUUUAUUUAUUAAAAACAAAAGCCCCAGCCCUGCCGAGGCCUGGGCGGCGUCCUCAGUCGGGUGGUCCCGGGGCCUUUGCGGUCCCGCCCGGCUGAGACGCUCGCCCCGACGCAUGGACCCGAGAGGCGACGACACGAGUGAAUAAAGUGCACAUGGACCCUG